GCUCCCUCGCUCCCUCGCUCCCUCCUGCCCUCCCGCUGCAGCUCCGGCUCCGCUCGACUUCCUGCCGGGCGCUGGCAAGCCGCGCGCUGCCUGGGGUCUCCGGGGGCCGCGCUUGCAGCUGGCCGAGUCCGGGCCAGCUGAGGGGCUGGCGGUGGGCGGGAGCGGUCGGCGGCCUCAGCCCCUUCAGAGAGCGACUUUCAAACUCGCGCCCGCGUCGCGGCAGCACCUGGGCAGCCCCGCACGCCGUGCGCGUCCCGAGCCCGCGGGGCAGCUACCGCUCGAAUCUCCCUGGGGUGCCCUCCCCAGGCAGCAAUGCCAGGAUGCCUGUGUCCACCUCCCUCCACCAGGAUGGCAGCCAGGAGCGGCCGGUGAGCCUGACCUCUACCACCUCCUCGUCGGGCUCCUCCUGUGACAGUCGCAGUGCCAUGGAGGAGCCCAGCAGCUCCGAGGCUCCCGCCAAGAAUGGGGCAGGCUCCCUGAGAAGCCGGCAUCUGCCCAACAGCAACAACAACUCCAGCAGCUGGUUGAACGUGAAGGGGCCCCUCUCCCCGUUCAACAGCCGGGCAGCGGCAGGGCCUGCACACCACAAGCUCAGCUACCUGGGCCGAGUGGUGCGGGAGAUCGUGGAGACAGAGCGCAUGUACGUACAGGACCUGCGCAGCAUCGUGGAGGACUACCUCUUGAAGAUCAUUGACACACCCGGGCUGCUGAAGCCAGAACAGGUCAGCGCCCUCUUUGGGAACAUAGAAAAUAUCUACGCGCUGAACAGCCAGCUCCUCAGAGACCUGGACAGCUGCAAUAGUGACCCCGUGGCUGUGGCCAGCUGCUUUGUGGAAAGGAGCCAAGAGUUUGAUAUCUACACUCAGUAUUGCAACAAUUACCCCAACUCCGUGGCCGCCCUGACGGAAUGCAUGCGGGACAAGCAGCAGGCCAAGUUCUUUCGGGACCGGCAGGAGCUGCUACAGCACUCGCUGCCCUUGGGCUCCUACCUGCUGAAGCCAGUCCAGCGCAUCCUCAAGUACCACCUGCUGCUCCAGGAAAUUGCCAAGCAUUUUGAUGAAGAAGAGGAUGGCUUUGAGGUGGUGGAGGAUGCCAUUGACACCAUGACCUGUGUGGCCUGGUACAUCAACGACAUGAAGAGGAGGCAUGAGCACGCGGUCCGGCUCCAGGAGAUUCAGUCACUCCUCAUCAACUGGAAGGGGCCCGACCUGACCACCUACGGGGAGCUUGUCCUGGAGGGCACAUUCCGCGUGCAUCGCGUGCGCAAUGAAAGGACCUUUUUCCUCUUUGACAAAACACUGCUUAUCACCAAGAAGCGGGGCGAUCACUUUGUCUACAAGGGCAACAUCCCGUGCUCCUCCCUGAUGCUGAUCGAAAGCACCAGAGACUCCCUGUGCUUCACUGUCACCCACUACAAGCACAGCAAGCAGCAGUACAGCAUCCAGGCCAAGACAGUGGAGGAGAAACGGAACUGGACUCACCACAUCAAGAGGCUCAUCCUAGAGAACCACCAUGCCACCAUUCCCCAGAAGGCCAAGGAAGCCAUCUUGGAAAUGGAUUCCUAUUAUCCCAAUCGGUACCGCUGCAGCCCAGAGCGGCUGAAGAAGGCUUGGUCCUCCCAGGAUGAGGUGUCCACCAAUGUGCGCCAGGGGCGCCGGCAAUCUGAGCCAACCAAACACCUGCUCAGGCAACUCAACGAGAAAGCCCGAGCAGCAGGAAUGAAGGGAAAGGGGCGCAGGGAGUCUGAAAGCUCCAGGAGCAGCAGAAGGCCCAGUGGCCGGUCUCCAACCAGUACUGAGAAGCGCAUGAGCUUCGAGUCCAUUUCUUCCCUGCCAGAGGUUGAGCCGGACCCUGAGGCUGGGAGUGAGCAAGAGGUAUUUUCUGCUGUGGAAGGGCCCAGUGCCGAGGAGACGCCUUCAGACACAGAAUCUCCAGAAGUCCUGGAGACACAGCUUGAUGCCCACCAGGGCCUUCUGGGGAUGGACCCCCCAGGUGACAUGGUGGACUUCGUGGCAGCUGAGAGCACUGAGGACCUUAAGGCCCUGAGCAGCGAGGAGGAAGAAGAAAUGGGAGGUGCCGCCCAGGAGCCUGAGAGCCUUCUGCCACCCUCUGUGCUGGACCAGGCCAGCGUCAUUGCGGAGCGAUUUGUCAGCAGCUUCUCUCGGCGGAGCAGCGUGGCACAGGAGGACAGCAAGUCCAGUGGCUUUGGGAGCCCGCGGCUGGUCAGCCGGAGCAGCAGCGUGCUCAGCCUGGAGGGCAGCGAGAAGGGCCUGGCCCGGCAUGGCAGUGCCACAGACUCCCUCAGCUGUCAGCUCUCCCCAGAAGUGGACAUCAGUGUGGGGGUGGCCACAGAGGACAGCCCUUCUGUCAAUGGGAUGGAGCCCCCAAGCCCAGGCUGCCCAGUGGAGCCUGACCGGUCUUCCUGCAAGAAGAAGGAAUCAGCACUCUCCACCCGAGACCGGCUGUUGCUAGACAAGAUUAAGAGCUAUUAUGAAAAUGCAGAACACCAUGAUGCAGGCUUCAGCGUCCGUCGCCGGGAGAGCCUCUCCUACAUCCCCAAAGGACUGGUAAGAAACUCCAUCUCCAGGUUCAACAGCCUUCCCCGGCCAGACCCAGAGCCAGUACCUCCAGUGGGGAGCAAGAGACAGGUGGGCUCCCGGCCGACUUCGUGGGCCCUGUUUGAGCUCCCAGGACCAAGCCAGGCAGUCAAAGGGGACCCACCUCCCAUCUCAGAUGCUGAGUUCCGCCCAUCUUCAGAAAUUGUGAAGAUCUGGGAGGGAAUGGAGUCUUCCGGAGGGAGCCCUGGGAAGGGGCCAGGCCAGGGCCAGGCCAAUGGCUUUGACCUGCAUGAGCCACUCUUCAUCCUGGAGGAGCAUGAGCUGGGAGCCAUCACAGAGGAGUCGGCCACUGCCUCCCCGGAAAGCUCCUCUCCCACUGAGGGGCGCAGCCCGGCCCACCUGGCCCGGGAGCUGAAAGAGCUGGUGAAGGAGCUGAGCAGCAGUACCCAGGGGGAGCUGGUGGCCCCACUGCACCCCCGCAUCGUGCAGCUCUCCCACGUAAUGGACAGCCACGUGAGCGAGCGCGUCAAGAACAAGGUCUACCAGCUGGCCCGCCAGUACAGCCUCCGGAUCAAGAGCAACAAGCCAGUGAUGGCCAGGCCACCACUGCAGUGGGAAAAGGUGGCCCCUGAGAGGGAUGGGAAGAGCCCCACUGUGCCCUGUCUACAGGAAGAGGCUGGAGAGCCAUUAGGUGGCAAAGGUAAGAGGAAGCCGGUGCUGUCUCUAUUUGACUAUGAGCAGCUGAUGGCCCAGGAGCACAGCCCUCCCAAGCCCUCCUCGGCUGGGGAGAUGUCACCACAGCGUUUCUUCUUCAACCCGUCUGCUGUCAGCCAGAGGACCACCUCGCCUGGGGGCCGGCCCUCCGCCCGGAGCCCCCUCAGCCCCACAGAGACCUUCAGCUGGCCCGACGUCCGUGAGCUCUGCUCCAAGUAUGCCUCCCGCGAUGAGGCACGCCGAGCAGGGGGCGGCCGGCCCCGCGGCCCACCCGUCAACAGGAGCCACUCGGUGCCGGAGAACAUGGUAGAGCCACCUCUGUCGGGCAGGGUGGGCCGCUGCCGCAGCCUGAGCACCAAGAGGGGCCGGGGAGGCGGAGAGGCUGCCCAAUCCCCUGGGCCUCUGCCCCAGAGCAAGCCGGAUGGAGGCGAGACCCUGUAUGUCACUGCAGACCUCACCCUGGAGGACAACCGGCGGGUGAUUGUCAUGGAGAAGGGACCCCUUCCCAGCCCCACUGCAGGGCUGGAGGAGAGCAGUGGCCAGGGACCAAGCUCACCGGUGGCCCUGCUGGGGCAGGUUCAGGACUUCCAGCAGUCUGCAGAGUGCCAGCCGAAGGAAGAGGGUUCCAGGGACCCGGCAGACCCGAGCCAGCAGGGCAGAGUGAGAAACCUUAGAGAGAAGUUCCAGGCCUUGAACUCUGUCGGUUGAUGCUGACUCCUGGGGGAGGGAGGAGUCAUGUUGGAGGUUGGGGAAGAACCUGGGCAUCCUUCCCCUCAAGCCUGGGCUCAUGGAGCCCCUGCCCAGGGCCCUCAGGUGGGCGGAAAGUCCAUCCCCUCCGCCCUUCAGGAAGGAUGCUCCCGUGUGCAGGGGUCUCCUGCCUGUGCCAUCCACUGGGGCUCGAGACAAUUUCCCACUCACCUGUGAGGCCGGUGUGGCUGCUUCCCUUGUAAAUAGUUGUUCUCUGGUAAGAAGCCAAAUAUUUAAGCUCACUUCUUCCCAGAGAGAGGAAGCUCUGCUCAGGCCUCCAGCGUUGGCUGGCCAUGGCCACAGCCAGAUGGAGGAGCCCAUCCCCAGGAGACUCAGGCAGUGGCCUGGAGAGGCUUUGUUCUGUAACGGUGCCUUUUCUUAGGGUCCAGGCAGGAAUGAAGCCAAUAAUUUAUUGCUUUCCAUUCUGUGGUAUGAUGUGCGUGUGCGUGAGUGUGUGGCCCCUGUUUAUUCCCCUCCUGUCAAGAAUGAAGUGGAUUCAGUUCAGGUACUUUUGAGGGUUGUUGUGCUGACCCUGUGGUUGUCGCUGAUGUACACACAUUUCAUUAUUUGCCAAUGGUGCAAUAACCACUGCUGACCAACCCACUAUGUGUGAACUCCUUCCUAGGCUUGGCUGGGGUAGGGAAGGUUAUUCAUGGGCCAGGGAUGUCUUAGGGAGAUGGAGACAUGGAGGUUGUUCCUUCCACACUCAAUUGUCACUUGGGCUUAUGAAACAUAAGGCACCCGGGUACUGGUGGGGGAGGUGGGGCAGGAGGAUGUGAGGGCGGGCUUUUUCUUUCUGCUGCCUAGACUCCCAUGGGCUUCUCUGUCUAGCAGCAGCCUGCUGUCCUGUCUAGGGUAGGGGGUCCCGCAUGCCAGCCUUUUGCUCUUUUCCCCAAGGGCCAGAGUUGGACCAAGAAAAAGGGAGGUGGUGAGGUGGAUAGACUGUUUUUCUCAUAAGCAGAUGCUCCCAGUAUCUGGUGCCUUUUGCGUUUCUCUCCGGUCCCCAGGAAACAUCCUAGAAGACAAGGAUUUUUUUUUUUUUUUUUUUUGAGACAGAGUCUUAUUCUGUCACCCAGGCUGGAGUGCAAUGGCGUGAUCUUGGCUUACUGCAACCUCCGCCUCCCAGGUUCAAGCAAUUCUCGUUGUCUCAGCCUCCCAGGUCGCUGGGACUACAGGCAUGAGCCACCACACCCAGCUAAUUUUUUGUAUUUUUAGUAGAGACGGGGUUUCGCCGUGUUGACCAGGCUGGUCUCGAACUUCUGACCUCAGGUGAUCCACCCACCUCGGCCUCCCAAAGUGCUGGGAUUACAGGGGUGAGCCACUGCAUGCGGCUGAAGGUAAGGAUUCUAAACUCGGAGACUAGAAAUGUCCUAAAGGUGUCUGCAACAUUGGAUGAGGAGUACAAGUGCAUUUUUCUGGGAUGAUUCCUCCCUUUUUAUCACAUUCUCAGAAGUAUCUUUGAUUCAGAAGAGUUAGGAAUGCCUCCCUAUUUCAGUUGGGUUUUCUGCCCUUUCUCCACAGAGGUCCAGACUCAUUUUGCUUAAUUUUUUUUCUAGCUGGGGCCUGGGAGGUAGAGGCUUCAGGGCCUGGGUGGUAGAGCUGCCUGACAAGUGUUCAGCAGGGCUGCUGGGUCAGGGCCCUGUGGGCCUUCUGACCCAACCUGAAGAUGGGUCUGCUAAGUCUAACAAGGUCAAGGGAAGAUCAGAGGGACCCAGAUUCUUUUUUAUCCCCCACUUGAAACGGAGUCUUGCUCUGUCGCCCAGGCUGGAGCGCAGUGGUGCAAUCUUGGCUCACUGCAACCUCCGCCUCCCUGACCCUCACACUGUCCAGUGCCCUUGUGGUUACUCAGCAUCAUAUCUUGAGACUGGCCUGGCAGGAGCCAGUGACUGUGGAAUGACCACAGAAGAUUCAGGGCAGCUGCCAGACCAGGGGCUAUCUCUGCCCUGCGCUGCUUCUGCUCAAGAGAGGUUGUCACUAGCCUCUGAUCUUCCCUUGAAGAACCCGACUGGGGCUCUUCAGAGGGUGGGGCCCAGGAAGUUGUAGUUAACCCCUUCCCCAGGCAGUCCUUACACGGCCAUCUAGGUAUGCCUGGGAACCUUGCACCAGGUCGGUGGUUCUCACUGGCUGCCCAUUGGAAUUAUCUGGGGAGCCUUCUGGAAACGCAGUGCUUACAUUCCAUCUCCCUAGACCAACAGAAACUGCCCUCUGGAGGUGAAUCCCAGGCUUAGAGAUUCUGAUGAUUCUGCGGUCCAGUGAGUGCUGAGAUCUGUCCUGAGCUCUGUGGGGAGGGGCCUGGACUGAUCACUGCUUGGAAAUGAUUUUGCCCUACAGUAGGCCUUCAAGUUGAUCAAAUGCAUGAAUGAGCAAGCUUUUCUUGGAGUUUGUGAUGAAGCCCAGGAACCGGGUGCUUGCAGUCGUCCCAUAAGGCUCCCAGGGACAAGCUAGAGAAUCUGGCUGUCCCUCUGUCUCCAUGGUGCCAGCCCUCUUAGGCUCAGUUCAAAGGGAGAGGAGGCUAGUUAAAUAAGAAACUGAGAGAAACAUGGAGCAUUAUUGAUUUAUUAGAAAAACUAGUAAAUGGGUUUCCUCUGGUUGGUGGAAGCACGGUUGAGCAGGUGGAGGACAGGACCCAGCUGGCCCCAGGGCCAGCCCCAGAUUGCAUGGUCUGUGCCCAACAGGGUUGCAUUCCUCUGCAGCCGCCGCCUCCUCAUUUCCUCCCUGAGCUUGUUUGUCCAAGCCACCAAGCCAUGUGGUCCCGCUGGCUUCAUCCUCCUCUGGAUUCCUGCCCCCCUCCCAUGAAGGGAGGAAGAGGAUUCAGGGUCAGCCUAGGGGACCCUGGCUCCCUCCGAUAGGCAGGAAGGAGGAGGGAUGCGGAGGAGAGGCUGAGCCUUCCACGGGCCUCCUGUUAGGGGUGUUGGUGGAGGCCAGGUUGGGGAGGGAAGCCUAAGGACCCUCCACACCUCCCACAGCCAGAGUCAGUUGAGGCUGGGACAAAGGGGAAGGAGAGAGGGAAGGAGGACCGCCUGACCUUGCCCAGAAGGAGCUUCCUCUAAACUGCCCUGGGAAGGAAGCCUGGUAUGCUGGUGUGGACUGGAGCUGUGUCAACCUCGUUUGGGAAUACUGUCAAAAGACUGUAGAGUAGAAUAAGGAGAGAAAAAAAAAAAAAGACCUUGCUAGGGCACUGGGAGAGCUUAGCCCUGGUGUGGCACACACAGGGUCUCCCAAAGCUGGAUGCCUGCAUUUUCAGUCUAGUUGGUCGAAUGUCUUGGAGCCUGGGUGACAGGAGGGAUGUGUGGGGAGCUGGCAACAGAAUGGUCACAUGCAGCUGGCUGCCCUGGACCAGGCCAGGGGACCUGGGGUGGUGAGAUGCUAGCUCUUCCACUAGAGCCCUUCCUUUCUCGGGUCUGUGGAGUUGCUUGCUGGAAAUGCCUCACUUCAGGUGCUGAUUUGGCACACGUGGAAGGGGGAGGGUGGGCCCUUGUCCCUAGGCUCCCUAAAGACUGGCCCAGGGAAACAGUUGAGGGAGAUGUUUGCCACCAUCUGCCCUUCAGCAAGGAACCUGCUCUCUGCCCCAGAGGAGGACAUGCCUGCAAGUGCACCAAAGGCCUACUUUAUUGCUAGGUGAGUGCAGUCACCUCACUGCCUUGGUUUCCCCAGAUACAGAAAGAGGCUGGUGAGUGAUACACACUAGGUUCCCUGUAUAGGGUCAUAUGUACCAAAGCCAAAUGAAGACCUUGCUCACCAGGGCGGGAACCUGGGGAUGUCAGGCUCCAUCGGAUGACGUCUUCCUUCCUGUGGCUCCUGCCUGCUGCAGUUGGUGUCACCCUGACAUAUAGUGUCAGGGCCACAGGGUGGAACUGAUUUCUGCCGGCACUGGUCAGCACUCAGGGUUCCUCAGGGGGCCUCAUUCUGGAUGCCUGCCCCUGUGGCUUCUACCUGAACCUCACCCACUUCAUCUCCAUGGAACUAAGGUCCUUCUCACGGGGAAGGUGAUAGAAACUUGACUGCAGGCCCUGGGGACUUUCAUGGUUUCCUUGGGGGAAAAUGCCUGCUGCCCUCCGCCCUCCCCCCCACCCCCGACCCGCUUGACUGCUCUCUUGGACCUAACCCUAGUUUGAUACUGGGCCAGAACUGUGUUGCUUUCGGAGUAGAGUGGUGGGGAAAAUAUGGAAUGAGCUUUCUCUUCCUCCAGAAGUAUGACCUGAGCAGCAAGGGGAAGGCCAUUCCUGGGGACGUUGGUUGCAGAGCUUCUGGUGCUCAGGGCUGGAGGGUGGUAGAUAUUUGACCUCUGUACUCAUGUGACCCCCUCCCCGCCAAGACCUGGGGCCAGGACGUGGAGAAGCUGAUCAAGGGGUACCACACCUUCAUGGCUCUGGCCCUGACAUUUGUCCCAGUUGUGCAGGAGUAGCUGUCACAUGGGUGGUGAUACCAAGACAUGGCUGCGUCUGCCACCCCGAGAAAACAGAUGAUCAACUUUACUGUCUGCCCAGCCAUUACCCUCCAAAGUCCCAGCUGCAGACAGGAUGCAAUUGAGCAUUUGGCUUUGGGAUGCUUUACUGCAGGUGCGGGGGGUAUCCAUCUUAUAUCUGGGGGCCCACACUGUCCCGUAGGGGGCCUAUGUCUGUUGGAUAUUGCUGGUUUGGCUGCCACUGGGAGUGGGGCGAGGGUCCCAGCAUUGAGAGGGAGAGCCUUAGGCAGUGUUGUGACGCACCUGUCACUCCUUCAGAUCAGAGCCCUGUGCCCUAGCCACGGUUUUCAAUGAGGAAUGGUCUGACCUUGCUGCCCUUCCUGGGACCGCCUGUGGUGGCACAAAGGGUGCUAGAGGCACUCAGCCAGGCCCUGCCAACCGUGGGAGGGUACCCUUUGAUCUGGGGGGAGAAGCAGAGAGGAGGGAUGUGGUGGCCCCUGAAGUGAGAGUCCCAGUUCUGCGGAAGCCCAGUGGGAAGGAGGCUGGCAGCUCCCAAGGCCCUGCACCCAGUCUGGUCCCCUCAGCCCCCCAGAGCCCCUGGCCCAGAGCUAGGGCUUUGUGGGCCACCUGAAGGCUCCUUCCUCAUGCCCCUAGGGGGCUGGCCAUGCAUUUCCAGUGUCUUCUUCCUUUCCCCUUUCCCUGGCUGCCACCAGGUGGGAGGUGACCCGAAGCAAGACUUGCUUUAGGAACGGGCAGCGUUUGAAGAACCCCAUCAGCCUUCUCCAGCUCUUUUUUUUUUUUUUUUUUGGUUGGGGGUAAGGGGCCUGUGCCCCCUCGGCUCAGGAGGAGGGUGGGAGAGGAGGGCGUGUGCCUCAGAGAACCGUUUCCUGCCCCCAGGCCUGGAGGCCCCAAAGGCGCCAGAGGAGCUGGGAGCCCCUGUCCCUGGAGCGGAGCCAGCGCGGGCGAGGGCAUGGAGGGGGCGUCGGCCCAGGACACGCGGGCGAAGGCAGCUUUUGCAGUGCAGCGUGGGGCCCGGGGGCCCGGCCCGCGACUCGACUCAUCUCGAUUCGACCGGCGGGCGGCGGCGAGAGGAGGCCAAGGCCUGGGCUGCCCGGUCUCUGCGCGUCCCGACUCCGCCGCGCCCGCCAGCCCCACCUGCUACUUCUUUUUGGGGAAGAAGCUGAAUCUCUUCUCCUUGUCUUUCUUGCCGAGGCUGGCGUCGGGGCCGGAGAGGGAAGGCAGGGGCAGGCUCUGCGCCUUGACGCGGAUGCUCUGGGACUCGUUGAUGGCGGUGCUCACGCCCUGCAGCCAGGACAGCAUCUCCUCCUGCGGGGCGGAGGGUCACGGUGGAGUCUGGAGGCCCACAGCCCCCCACCUCCCGGGCCAGGCAACAAUGGUGGGGGCUCUUGGGACUGCCCCUUCUGAGGGGGCCUCCAGGGCAAGCGGCCUGGGGUCCUCCACCUACCCCCUUCUUAGCCAGGUCUGGGCUAGGCUGCCCGCGCUUACCUCAUCCUUGCCAUGGAAGAGCCACUCGCUGCCAUUACUCAGCCUAGGAGGACAAAGGGUUUCCUGUCAUGGAGACACCUCUGGAGGGGGCGCUGGGCAGAGGGCUGGCUCUGAUCCCACAAUACCCUGAGCCGAACAUCCAGACCCCUCUCAGGCAGCCCAGCACUUUCUGAGAGGUCAAAGUCUGGACCAUCAGCCUCUUUGAUUUGAAAAACCCCUGAGGAGCAGCUCAGGCCUGGCACUGGUCCCCUACAGAGGGCCUCUGCCCUGCCACUAAUGCCAAAUCAAGCCAUCAACCCGAGCUUUCAAAGGCCAGGAAGGCCUCACCUCAGCUUAAAGACGUGCUUCUUCUUCUUGUAGUUGGCAGCAAUCUCACAGAUGGCAUGUCUCAGGGCCAGGGGUUCCUCCCCAUGGUAGGGCAUCCCCAGGGCCAGGUUCUUGGCAUCCUUGUAGAAGGUUAGCUCACUGUUCCUGAGCACACAGUACAGGUUGUUCCAGGACCUGCAAAGAUGCAGACAGGCAGGUCACCCACAUCCUGAUAUGGUAUCUCUAGAGUCAAUUCCUAUAGCUUCACCAUUAAAAAAAAUUACACCAUG